AGGCUCCAACAUCCUCCCCCUGUCAAGAUGUGGCACCUCAAACUUUGUGCAGUCCUCAUGAUCUUCCUGUUGCUGUUGGGCCAGAUAGAUGGCUCCCCAAUACCAGAAGUGAGUUCGGCAAAGAGAAGGCCACGGAGAAUGACCCCAUUUUGGAGAGGGGUUUCCCUCAGGCCUAUUGGAGCCUCCUGCCGGGAUGAUUCUGAGUGUAUCACAAGGCUAUGCAGAAAAAGACGCUGUUCCUUAAGUGUGGCCCAGGAAUGAUGUACAUACCAGGGAAAGAAAGGACAGCAGUCACCUCCGACAAUGCUCCGUUCUAUGGAAUAUUGAUUAACUGCAUUUUGGCUGGAGACACCCAAGUGAAGCAAUCUUGUAUUUUUAAUAUUUAAAGGCAGAUGUACGCUUUAAAUUGGUCUCCAUUUCUUCUUAGAAUGUUGAUAUAUGGAUAAGCAUAACUAAACUUGUCAAUUUAGAGUUUAUUUUUCUAUGGAUACUAUUAAAUGUCUCAAAUUGAAAUUUUAGCAGUCUGGAAUUCAAGCUUUUGAGGGAAAGAAGGAUUCAUUUUGUAUACUAAAGAAAAAAACAGCAUUGCCCAAUAAUGUGUUAACUUCUCAAUCUGGAAAGUGUAGUGAGAGCUACAUAAUCAAUAGCUACGUAAUCAACUUCAGCAAGUUCCUAAGCUGUGGCCCUGGAUCCCUUCACUCCAUACUCUUCAGGGAGGUGUCAAAGGUGGUCAAGCUUGGGAGGCUGAGGCAGGAGAAUCACUUGAACCUGGGAGGUGGAGGUUGCAGUGAGCCAAGAUCAUGCCACUGCACCCCAGCCUGGGUGACAUAGAGAGACUCUGUCUCAAAAAAAAAAAAAAAA